AGUUUCCUUCAGCGGGGCACUGGGAAGCGCCAUGGCACUGCAGGGCAUCUCGGUCGUGGAGCUGUCCGGCCUGGCCCCGGGCCCGUUCUGUGCUAUGGUCCUGGCUGACUUCGGGGCGCGUGUGGUACGCGUGGACCGGCCCGGCUCCCGCUACGACGUGAGCCGCUUGGGCCGGGGCAAGCGCUCGCUAGUGCUGGACCUGAAGCAGCCGCGGGGAGCCGCCGUGCUGCGGCGUCUGUGCAAGCGGUCGGAUGUGCUGCUGGAGCCCUUCCGCCGCGGUGUCAUGGAGAAACUCCAGCUGGGCCCAGAGAUUCUGCAGCGGGAAAAUCCAAGGCUUAUUUAUGCCAGGCUGAGUGGAUUUGGCCAGUCAGGAAGCUUCUGCCGGUUAGCUGGCCACGAUAUCAACUAUUUGGCUUUGUCAGGUGUUCUCUCAAAAAUUGGCAGAAGUGGUGAGAAUCCGUAUGCCCCGCUGAAUCUCCUGGCUGACUUUGCUGGUGGUGGCCUUAUGUGUGCACUGGGCAUUAUAAUGGCUCUUUUUGACCGCACACGCACUGGCAAGGGUCAGGUCAUUGAUGCAAAUAUGGUGGAAGGAACAGCAUAUUUAAGUUCUUUUCUGUGGAAAACUCAGAAAUUGAGUCUGUGGGAAGCACCUCGAGGACAGAACAUGUUGGAUGGUGGAGCACCUUUCUAUACGACUUACAGGACAGCAGAUGGGGAAUUCAUGGCUGUUGGAGCAAUAGAACCCCAGUUCUACGAGCUGCUGAUCAAAGGACUUGGACUAAAGUCUGAUGAACUUCCCAAUCAGAUGAGCAUGGAUGAUUGGCCAGAAAUGAAGAAGAAGUUUGCAGAUGUAUUUGCAGAGAAGACGAAGGCAGAGUGGUGUCAAAUCUUUGACGGCACAGAUGCCUGUGUGACUCCGGUUCUGACUUUUGAGGAGGUUGUUCAUCAUGAUCACAACAAGGAACGGGGCUCGUUUAUCACCAGUGAGGAGCAGGACGUGAGCCCCCGCCCUGCACCUCUGCUGUUAAACACCCCAGCCAUCCCUUCUUUCAAAAGGGAUCCUUUCAUAGGAGAACACACUGAGGAGAUACUUGAAGAAUUUGGAUUCAGCCGCGAAGAGAUUUAUCAGCUUAACUCAGAUAAAAUCAUUGAAAGUAAUAAGGUAAAAGCUAGUCUCUAACUUCCAGGCCCACGGCUCAAGUGAAUUUGAAUACUGCAUUUACAGUGUAGAGUAACACAUAACAUUGUAUGCAUGGAAACAUGGAGGAACAGUAUUACAGUGUCCUACCACUCUAAUCAAGAAAAGAAUUACAGACUCUGAUUCUACAGUGAUGAUUGAAUUCUAAAAAUGGUUAUCAUUAGGGCUUUUGAUUUAUAAAACUUUGGGUACUUAUACUAAAUUAUGGUAGUUAUUCUGCCUUCCAGUUUGCUUGAUAUAUUUGUUGAUAUUAAGAUUCUUGACUUAUAUUUUGAAUGGGUUCUAGUGAAAAAGGAAUGAUAUAUUCUUGAAGACAUCGAUAUACAUUUAUUUACACUCUUGAUUCUACAAUGUAGAAAAUGAGGAAAUGCCACAAAUUGUAUGGUGAUAAAAGUCACGUGAAACAGAGUGAUUGGUUGCAUCCAGGCCUUUUGUCUUGGUGUUCAUGAUCUCCCUCUAAGCACAUUCCAAACUUUAGCAACAGUUAUCACACUUUGUAAUUUGCAAAGAAAAGUUUCACCUGUAUUGAAUCAGAAUGCCUUCAACUGAAAAAAACAUAUCCAAAAUAAUGAGGAAAUGUGUUGGCUCACUACGUAGAGUCCAGAGGGACAGUCAGUUUUAGGGUUGCCUGUAUCCAGUAACUCGGGGCCUGUUUCCCCGUGGGUCUCUGGGCUGUCAGCUUUCCUUUCUCCAUGUGUUUGAUUUCUCCUCAGGCUGGUAGCAAGUUCUGGAUCUUAUACCCAACACACAGCAACAUCCAGAAAUAAAGAUCUCAGGACCCCCCAGCAAGUCGUUUUGUGUCUCCUUGGACUGAGUUAAGUUACAAGCCUUUCUUAUACCUGUCUUUGACAAAGAAGACGGGAUUGUCUUUACAUAAAACCAGCCUGCUCCUGGAGCUUCCCUGGACUCAACUUCCUAAAGGCAUGUGAGGAAGGGGUAGAUUCCACAAUCUAAUCCGGGUGCCAUCAGAGUAGAGGGAGUAGAGAAUGGAUGUUGGGUAGGCCAUCAAUAAGGUCCAUUCUGCGCAGUAUCUCAACUGCCGUUCAACAAUCGCAAGAGGAAGGUGGAGCAGGUUUCUUCAUCUUACAGUUGAGAAAACAGAGACUCAGAAGGGCUUCUUAGUUCAUGUUUCCCUUAGCGCCUCAGUGAUUUUUUCAUGGUGGCUUAGGCCAAAAGAAAUAUCUAACCAUUCAAUUUAUAAAUAAUUAGGUCCCCAACGAAUUAAAUAUUAUGUCCUACCAACUUAUUAGCUGCUUGAAAAAUAUAAUACACAUAAAUAAAAAAAUAUAUUUUUCAUUUCUAUUUCAUUGUUAAUCACAACUACUUACUAAGGAGAUGUAUGCACCUAUUGGACACUGUGCAACUUCUCACCUGGAAUGAGAUUGGACACUGCUGCCCUCAUUUUCUGCUCCAUGUUGGUGUCCAUAUAGUACUUGAUUUUUUAUCAGAUGGCCUGGAAAACCCAGUCUCACAAAAAUAUGAAAUUAUCAGAAGGAUUAUAGUGCAAUCUUAUGUUGAAAGAAUGAACUACCUCACUAGUAGUUCACGUGAUGUCUGACAGAUGUUGAGUUUCAUUGUGUUUGUGUGUUCAAAUUUUUAAAUAUUCUGAGAUACUCUUGUGAGGUCACUCUAAUGCCCUGGGUGCCUUGGCACAGUUUUAGAAAUACCAGUUGAAAAUAUUUGCUCAGGAAUAUGCAACUAGGAAGGGGCAGAAUCAGAAUUUAAGCUUUCAUAUUCUAGCCUUCAGUCUUGUUCUUCAACCAUUUUUAGGAACUUUCCCAUAAGGUUAUGUUUUCCAGCCCAGGCAUGGAGGAUCACUUGAGGCCAAGAGUUCGAGACCAGCCUGGGGAACUUGGCUGGACCUCCGUUUCUACGAAAUAAAAAUAAAAAAAUUAUCCAGGUAUGGUGGUGUGUGCCUGUAGUCCUAUCUACUCAAGGGUGGGGCAGGAGGAUCACUUGAGCCCAGGAAUUUGAGGCCACAGUGAAUUAGGAUUGCACCACUGCACUCUAGCCCAGGCAACAGAACAAGAACCUGUCUCUAAAUAAAUAAAUAAAAAUAAUAAUAAUAAAAAAGAUGUUUUCCCUACAACUCAGACUUUUCAUUUGAACUCGGUCCAGCAAGGAAAAUAUAACCCACUCGAAGUCUUUAAAACAGAGGAAAUUUAAUAUAAAGAAUUCCACUGGUGACGAAAGAGCAGAGAAGCCCAGAAGAUAGUGAGGCAACCCUGAUAGGAACAUAACUAGGAAGCCAAGACCACUCCUAUGGUUGCAGGGGUGAUGGGAAAGCUGGUGUACUUGGACCCAGAAGCCAAAGUUGCUGCACCCACCUUGGAGACAUAGACACUGGCAGUAAUACCUCAGGGAGAAGAAAGAAAUCUAGGGAAAUAUCCUGGCUUCUUUCCUUCUCUCUCUCCCCUAGUCUUCCUACCAGUGUCUCCCAUUAGCCAAAUCUACCUAGAAGCCAGAAAACAAGGGAACCCUGGAAAUGUAGCCCCAUAAGAUAAAGAGCACCAAAGGAAAUAGAUCUGAGCAGACAGGCAGCACAAAAUGCAGUGUGUAUGGUUUAUUCACUCAGUAAUUCCUUUAGCAAAUGUUUAUUGAGGAUCUACUAGGUGCCAGGUAUCAUGAUACUUGCUGGGGAUACCAUAAUGAACAAAACAGACCUGUUCUCCGCUCUUGAGGAAAUCAAAGACAAACACAGGAUAUGGAAUAAACCCAGAAUUAUCUCAUUGUAAAAUGUGUUAAGUACCACGAGGAGAAAUAUCAGGGCGAUCUGACACAGCUAAUGAUUUGAAGAAGGGUGUGACCUGCCACCAUUUUAAAUCUAGUUAUUUCACUCCUGAGCUGUGUGUGUGGAAAACUUGUAGUAAAAAAUAGAAUGUCUAUAUUUAUAAAAAGUUUAUGAAAAGA